AUGCCAACAGGAAAUGACGUGGAAAGAGAUGACUUCUUUGGAGCAGCCAUGAUGGAGUUAGAAAGGAGUUGGAGGAUGAGCAGGGCCUGGGAGUCCCUCAUCGCUCAGACUGUACUGAUACAGGAGUCUCUCAGAAAGACAACAUUUUCUCCUCCUAAAGGAAGCAGGAUACUACUCCAGGCACGGGCAUUAGGGGCUCCCACAGGCUGGACAGGCCUUGGACUUUCCUGGUUGAACCGUGAGGCCGCGGUGUCAGUCCACACUCCACUGUGGGUGGCGGGUUCGGCCCCGCGAGGAGGCGCCGCUCUCAAACCCCACGGUCCCGCGCAGCGAAGAGGCGAGGCGGCCGCGGAAGGCAGGCGCAGCCCACUCUUCCCGAGAGGCCCCGACAUCUCCCGGGUGAGUCCCGAAAAGCGCGCGGGGACUCCGGCUGAGCGCUGGGCCCCUCCGGCGGCCAGUCCCGCGGCUCUGGGGCGCCCGGACCGAGCAAAGGUCCCGGCGGGCGGGCCCUCUCUCCGCCCUCCCCAAGCGCCCGCCCCCCGCCGGCCCAGCGCAGGCUCCUCCGACUCCGCCAGCGCAGGGGGCGCGGCUGCCGGGGACCCAGCAGCGGGCGCGCGGGUAAGUGCGCGGCGGGCGCGGGCUGCGGGAUCCGCUCCGGGCUCCACUCCGGAUCCUCUUUGGUCUGUUUGGGUGUCCCGGGCCGGGGGCAGCCGAGGCCGCGCGGCGCUUUCUCUCUGGGCCACCCUCCCCUCGCUCCUUCCUAGGGGAGACGAAUCGAUUGGCUGCCCGGCCGCCGGAACGGCAGGUCCCGUCGCUCCCCUCGCCUCCCGCAUUCCCGGCCCGGUCCCCUCCCAUCACCGCGUCCCGCCCCAACUCGCAGUCAGCAUCCCCUUCCCAUCCUCUCCCCGUCCCCGCUGCCACUUCCUUCCUUGGAUGUUGGAAGCGCAGCUGGUAUUUUCGUUCUCCCAACCCCCCAAACCCCCCCUCCCCAUUCGUUCAUCCUUUGUGUUCCGGUCUCUUCUCUGGGUGCUGCGGAGGCUCUCCCGGCUCGGGGGCGUGUGUGCAGGGAGGCGGACCGCGGAACAGAUACGGAGUUCAGUCUCUCUGGACGGAAAAAAGUCCCCCUCCACUUUGCUCCGGUAUCUAGAGAGCUCCUAGCUUGGGGAGGAGGCCAAGCCCCACUCGGUGUGCCUGGCAUGCGCUGGAAUGGCUCUCAAGAGCUGCCCGCGUGGCUUCCUUUGGUCUCCAUUUGAGGACCUCUGACCCUUUCCAGAGCCGCUUGCCGUCUGCACCCCGAGGGGAAAGACUAGAGGGCACCUCUUAGAAAAGCGCUGGUUGUGGACUGAACACACCGACCACCCACUCCUCCAGAGUCUACUCUGUCCAGAAUAGUGAAUGGGAUAAUGAAAGGGAUGGAUGGCUUGCGGUCGCUGUCCUCGAGACGCAGGCAGGUGGGGCAAGUCCAAGUGGAAUGAAAGGAGUGCUGUGGGGUUGGAGAAGCAGCUGAAGAGUGAAAUUAAUUGUCUUCACAAUCUACCACCACCAAGCUCUUUUUCUAAAGGAGAAGUUGAGCCCAGACCAUUAGGUAGAUCUGAGAGAGAAAGGGCCCAACCCCCUAGCCACGGUCCCUUGGCUAGGUUCUUUGUUAUUGUUGAGAGAGGGUCUCGCUCUGUCACCAAGGCUGGAGUGC